AUCUCUGCACCCUGAGGGCCCCGGGAGGAGGCGCGGGCGCGCCGGGAGGGACCGGCGGCGGCAUGGGCCGGGGGCCCUGGGAUGCGGGCCCGUCUCGCCGCCUGCUGCCGCUGUUGCUGCUGCUCGGCCUGGCCCGCGGCGCCGCGGGAGCGCCGGGCCCCGACGGUUUAGACGUCUGUGCCACUUGCCAUGAACAUGCCACAUGCCAGCAAAGAGAAGGGAAGAAGAUCUGUAUUUGCAACUAUGGAUUUGUAGGGAACGGGAGGACUCAGUGUGUUGAUAAAAAUGAGUGCCAGUUUGGAGCCACUCUUGUCUGUGGGAACCACACAUCUUGCCACAACACCCCCGGGGGCUUCUAUUGCAUUUGCCUGGAAGGAUAUCGAGCCACAAACAACAACAAGACAUUCAUUCCCAACGAUGGCACCUUUUGUACAGACAUAGAUGAGUGUGAAGUUUCUGGCCUGUGCAGGCAUGGAGGGCGAUGCGUGAACACUCAUGGGAGCUUUGAAUGCUACUGUAUGGAUGGAUACUUGCCAAGGAAUGGACCUGAACCUUUCCACCCGACCACCGAUGCCACAUCAUGCACAGAAAUAGACUGUGGUACCCCUCCUGAGGUUCCAGAUGGCUAUAUCAUAGGAAAUUAUACGUCUAGUCUGGGCAGCCAGGUUCGUUAUGCUUGCAGAGAAGGAUUCUUCAGUGUUCCAGAAGAUACAGUUUCAAGCUGCACAGGCCUGGGCACAUGGGAGUCCCCAAAAUUACAUUGCCAAGAGAUCAACUGUGGCAACCCUCCAGAAAUGCGGCACGCCAUCUUGGUAGGAAAUCACAGCUCCAGGCUGGGCGGUGUGGCUCGCUAUGUCUGUCAAGAGGGCUUUGAGAGCCCUGGAGGAAAGAUCACUUCUGUUUGCACAGAGAAAGGCACCUGGAGAGAAAGUACUUUAACAUGCACAGAAAUUCUGACAAAGAUUAAUGAUGUAUCACUGUUUAAUGAUACCUGUGUGAGAUGGCAAAUAAACUCAAGAAGAAUAAACCCCAAGAUCUCAUAUGUGAUAUCCAUAAAAGGACAACGGUUGGACCCUAUGGAAUCAGUUCGUGAGGAGACAGUCAACUUGACCACAGACAGCAGGACCCCAGAAGUGUGCCUAGCCCUGUACCCAGGCACCAACUACACCGUGAACAUCUCCACAGCACCUCCCAGGCGCUCGAUGCCAGCCGUCAUCGGUUUCCAGACAGCUGAAGUUGAUCUCUUAGAAGAUGAUGGAAGUUUCAAUAUUUCAAUAUUUAAUGAAACUUGUUUGAAAUUGAACAGGCGUUCUAGGAAAGUUGGAUCAGAACACAUGUACCAAUUUACCGUUCUGGGUCAGAGGUGGUAUCUGGCUAACUUUUCUCAUGCAACAUCGUUUAACUUCACAACGAGGGAACAAGUGCCUGUAGUGUGUUUGGAUCUGUACCCUACGACUGAUUAUACGGUGAAUGUGACCCUGCUGAGAUCUCCUAAGCGGCACUCAGUGCAAAUAACAAUAGCAACUCCCCCAGCAGUAAAACAGACCAUCAGUAACAUUUCAGGAUUUAAUGAAACCUGCUUGAGAUGGAGAAGCAUCAAGACAGCUGAUAUGGAGGAGAUGUAUUUAUUCCACAUUUGGGGCCAGAGAUGGUAUCAGAAGGAAUUUGCCCAGGAAAUGACCUUUAAUAUCAGUAGCAGCAGCCGAGAUCCCGAGGUGUGCUUGGACCUACGUCCGGGUACCAACUACAAUGUCAGUCUCCGGGCUCUGUCUUCGGAACUUCCUGUGGUCAUCUCCCUGACAACCCAGAUAACAGAGCCUCCCCUCCCGGAAGUAGAAUUUUUUACGGUGCACAGAGGACCUCUACCACGCCUCAGACUGAGGAAAGCCAAGGAGAAAAAUGGACCAAUCAGUUCAUAUCAGGUGUUAGUGCUUCCCCUGGCCCUCCAAAGCACAUUUUCUUGUGAUUCUGAAGGCGCUUCCUCCUUCUUUAGCAACGCCUCUGAUGCUGAUGGAUACGUGGCUGCAGAACUACUGGCCAAAGAUGUUCCAGAUGAUGCCAUGGAGAUACCUAUAGGAGACAGGCUGUACUAUGGGGAAUAUUAUAAUGCACCCUUGAAAAGAGGGAGUGAUUACUGCAUUAUAUUACGAAUCACAAGUGAAUGGAAUAAGGUGAGAAGACACUCCUGUGCAGUUUGGGCUCAGGUGAAAGAAAUACCUUGUAACUGUAAUUUCCUGAGGCUGCAUAUCCACAGGGCCAACUCAGGGGACACACAGAUUCGUCACUCAUGCUGCUGCAGAUGGCGGGUGUUGGACUGGGUUCCCUGGCUGUUGUGAUCAUUCUCACAUUCCUCUCCUUCUCAGCGGUGUGAUGGCAGAUGGACACUGAGUGGGGAGGAUGCACUGCUGCUGGGCAGGUGUUCUGGCAGCUUCUCAGGUGCCCGCACAGAGGCUCCGUGUGACUUCCGUCCAGGGAGCAUGUGGGCCUGCAACUUUCUCCAUUCCCAGCUGGGCCCCAUUCCUGGAUUUAAGAUGGUGGCUAUCCCUGAGGAGUCACCAUAAGGAGAAAACUCAGGAAUUCUGAGUCUUCCCUGCUACAGGACCAGUUCUGUGCAAUGAACUUGAGACUCCUGAUGUACACUGUGAUAUUGACCGAAGGCUACAUACAGAUCUGUGAAUCUUGGCUGGGACUUCCUCUGAGUGAUGCCUGAGGGUCAGCUCCUCUAGACAUUGACUGCAAGAGAAUCUCUGCAACCUCCUAUAUAAAAGCAUUUCUGUUAAUUCAUUCAGAAUCCAUUCUUUACAAUAUGCAGUGAGAUGGGCUUAAGUUUGGGCUAGAGUUUGACUUUAUGAAGGAGGUCAUUGAAAAAGAGAACAGUGACGUAGGCAAAUGUUUCAAGCACUUUAGAAACAGUACUUUUCCUAUAAUUAGUUGAUAUACUAAUGAGAAAAUAUACUAGCCUGGCCAUGCCAAUAAGUUUCCUGCUGUGUCUGUUAGGCAGCAUUGCUUUGAUGCAAUUUCUAUUGUCCUAUAUAUUCAAAAGUAAUGUCUACAUUCCAGUAAAAAUAUCCCGUAAUUAA